CGGAAGUCGGCGGCGGUGGCGGAGGCGGUGAGUGCGCGGCUCCGGGGCUGGCCGACUCCGCUAGUGGCCCGGCCGGCCUGGGCUCGGGGGCUCCGGGCUCUGGGCUCUGGGUGCGCGGACCGGGCCAGGCUGCUUGAAGACCUCGCGACCUGUGUCAGCAGAGCCGCCCUGCACCACCAUGUGCAUCAUCUUCUUUAAGUUUGAUCCUCGCCCUGUUUCCAAAAACGCGUACAGGUAACCCCCUCGCUCUGCAUCUGCUGCGCCCUGCAGGGUCCUGGGUGCCCAGCCAGUUCUCAUGCCACCCAAGCUGCUGUGUGCAGGAAGGUGUGUGGGCCAGGACGGGGCUGCACAGGCCUGGCACUGCCCUCCAGGACAGGGUCACUCAGUGUGGGAUGCUGUCAGAAUGCCUCUCGGGGCGGGGACUCCAGUCAAUGUACAAAGACGUGAAGACUCAGCCACAGAAGGCAGCCACAGGCUCAUCUUGGCAGCCAACAGGGAUGAAUUCUACAGCCGACCCUCCAAGUUAGCUGACUUCUGGGGGAACAACAACGAGAUCCUCAGUGGGCUGGACAUGGAGGAAGGCAAGGAAGGAGGCACAUGGCUGGGCAUCAGCACACGUGGCAAGCUGGCAGCACUCACCAACUACCUGCAGCCGCAGCUGGACUGGCAGGCCCGAGGGCGAGGUGAACUUGUCACCCACUUUCUGACCACUGACGUGGACAGCUUGUCCUACCUGAAGAAGGUCUCUAUGGAGGGCCAUCUGUACAAUGGCUUCAACCUCAUAGCAGCCGACCUGAGCACAGCAAAGGGAGACGUCAUUUGCUACUAUGGGAACCGAGGGGAGCCUGAUCCUAUCGUUUUGACGCCAGGCACCUACGGGCUGAGCAACGCGCUGCUGGAGACUCCCUGGAGGAAGCUGUGCUUUGGGAAGCAGCUCUUCCUGGAGGCUGUGGAACGGAGCCAGGCGCUGCCCAAGGAUGUGCUCAUCGCCAGCCUCCUGGAUGUGCUCAACAAUGAAGAGGCGCAGCUGCCAGACCCGGCCAUCGAGGACCAGGGUGGGGAGUACGUGCAGCCCAUGCUGAGCAAGUACGCGGCUGUGUGCGUGCGCUGCCCUGGCUACGGCACCAGGUAUUGCAGCACCGUGGGUGCGCCACCUCCUAUCCCAUGUCCCACCUCCCACGCUAGAGGGCCGGCAAAGAAGCCAAGUGCCCAUAGCCAGAGCCAGGCUUCUUCCUCGCCUGAGUGGAUUCCAGAGCUUCUGCCCUGUCCAGACGCAGCUGCAGGAACCAACACUAUCAUCCUGGUAGAUGCGGACGGCCACGUGACCUUCACUGAGCGUAGCAUGAUGGACAAGGACCUCUCCCACUGGGAGACCAGAACCUAUGAGUUCACACUGCAGAGCUAACCCCACCUCUGGGCCUGGCCAGUGGGCUCCUGGGGGGCCCUGCCUUGAGGGGCACUGUGGACAGGAAACCUUCCUUUGCCAUACUGCAUUGCACUGCCCGUGGCUUGGCCAGCAUCCCCCGGAUCAGGGCCCUGUGGUUUGCGUGUUACCCAUCUGUGUCCCCAUGCCCAGUUCAGGGUCUGCCUUUAUGCCAGUGAGGAGCAGCAGAGUCUGAUACUAGGUCUAGGACCGGCCGAGGUAUACCAUGAACAUGUGGAUACACCUGAGCCCACUCUUGCACAUGUACACAGGCACUCACAUGGCACACACAUACACUCCUGCGUGUGCACAAGCACACACAUGCAAGCCAUAUACAUGGACACCGACACAGGCACAUGUACGUGCACAGGUGUGCUACACAUGUGCACACAUGCACAGUUGCACAGACACACACACACAGGUGCACACACACGAUGCCGAACAAGGCAGAAGGGCGACUCUCACCUCUCAUGUGCUUCUGGCCAGUAGGUCUUUGUUCUGGUCCAACGACAGGAGUAGGCUUGUAUUUAAAAGCGGCCCCUCCUCUCCUGUGGCCACAGAACACAGGCGUGCUUGGACUCUUGACAAGCAGACCUGCUCCUGCAGAGGAGACAGCCACAUUUGGAAUUGGGCACCGAGAAGACCUGAGAAAAACCCACUCUCUCUUUUUUUUUUUUUUGAGACGGAGUCUUGCUCUGUCACCCAGGCUGGAGUGCAGUGGCACGAUCUCGGCUCACUGCAACCUCCGCCUCCCAAGUUCAAGCAAUUCUCCUGCCCCAGCCUCCUGAUUAGCUGGGAUUACAGGCGUGUGCCACCAUGCCCAGCUAAUUUUUGUGUUUUUAGUAGAGACGGGGUUUCACCAUGUUGGUCAGGCUGGUCUUGAACUCCUGACGUGGUGAUCCACCUGCCUCGGCCUCCCAAAGUGCUGGGAUUACAGGCGUGAGCCACCACGCCUGGCCGAAAAACCCACUCUCAUAACAGAAGUGCAGACUCAUUGCUAGAUUCAGUGCCCUUGAGUGUGCCAGAGGUCCUCUGUGUUUGAGACAAUCCUGUGUGUGCCAGGAGGCUCCGUGUGCACCAGGGGCUCUCAGAAUCCCGCUUACCCAGCUGGAGACCAUGCCUCUGGCAGCCCCAUCUCAGCCAGCCCUGCUCUCUCCCUCUUCCCUCCAGGUGAGGCAAACUUCAUAGGAAUCUGUACCUGAAUGUGAGCUCCUGAUAAUAAAACUCUGAGGCUUUGGUGAGCGCAUUUCGAGGCCUUUCCCUUGUAUGCAGGGUGCCAGUGGGAGCUGCUAUGUCUCCUGUGCAGCCAGACACCCUGGACGAGGCCCUUCCCACCUCCCCCUUUCCUCACGGCUUCUUCAGCACCACAUGUGGAUGCCUGUGGGUCAGUCCAUCUGUCCAUGGGCAGGGGCCGCUGUGAGAGACCCCAUGCGCGUGGGAUGUGGUAGAUGCUGAUUAUGGGGCCAGCCACCCAUACAGGUCUAUCAGGUCGCAAUGGAGGCCCCACUGGAGCGGGAGGCAGGCUGGCCUGGACUUCUGUUGGAUGAUGGGGGCCAGGGGAUGGUAGGAGGGGCAGGAGAGCAGGUCUGCAUCUGUCUCAGCCCCAGGAGCUCCUGGUUUGGGGCCAGCUCUAAGGAGCUUCAUCCCUGAGCCUGGCCGAGUAUAAGGGGGUCCCGGAUAUCCAAUGCUGAGACCUAGACUUUUCUAAGCCUCUGCACCCAACCCCUAACUUGGCCUUUUCAGACCCAUGAGAGUGCAGGGUGGGUGUGGACCUGCGCCAGGGCUUCCCAGCCUGAUUGUGACAUGAUGUGAGUCCACCUAGGGAGGAGCAGGGGCCUCCCCGUCUCUUCCCCUUCUUGCCCAGACCACUUUGCUGGGCUCAGAGCCUUCCAUGGCUCACUUUGAACUCAGAAGAGUUUCCCAGCUGCGACCCAGGCUGCACCCCCAGGCCUGAGGAGAAACUGAGGCCCCACAUCCCAUACGUGUCCUCUGAGUCAGGACAACAGGCUCCCGGCUGGGGGCACUGCCCUUGCUGCCAACACAUUCACCUGCCCCAGUGGCUACCAUGUCCUGUGCCGGUGACCAGUGCCAGUCCCCAACCUGGAUGGUGCCCUGCCCUCAUGAAGAGCCCCCCGGAUGUUCACCUCUGCCCAGAGACCCGGCCUGCCCAGGAAGAGCAGUCUCUGCUCUUGUGUGGGUCCCUCUGCCCCCACCCUGCCCAGGGCUCCCCAGCAGCCUGAGGCCCCUAAGGAAGAACAGCCCUCAAUGGUGAUUCUAUUGGUGUUAUGAGUUGUGUCCCCAAAGAGAUAUAUCAGUGUCCUGACCCACAGUACCUCAGAAUGUGACUGCAUUUGGAGAUAGGGUUCUUCCAGGGGUAACCAAGGUAGAAUGAGGUCGUUAGUGUGGGCCCUAAUCCAAUAUGACGGCUAUCCUUAUAAAAAGAGGAACAUUUAGGCUGGAUACAGUGGCUCAUGCCUAUAAUCC